GUUCUAUAAAGGAAACUUCCCUAGAAAGAAACCACUUCUAAAUGGAAUAAUUAAAAUAAUUUGUUAGAAACUUUAAGUUACCCUAUGAGCUCCUAGUAACACUGUUUUCAAGCUCAUAGGUUAAUUGUUAAGCCCUUUUGCUCCGAGUUGAACUGAUCAAAUGGCUCUGUGUAAAAGGUAACAGUGUAGAAUCCUCUUUGAGAAAUAGCAUGUAAACUUGGGAGAAAUGGCCUAAGCCCACGGUUCUCAAGUCACUGAGACAGUUGAAAAAGCCCCCUCAGGUGGUGAGAAUGGGAUAAUAUUUUAUUAUAUCUCUAAGAUGCCUCAAAUCCAAAGAGAUAAUUAAAUUUGGAAUUUUAUUAGUUUCACCUAAUAGUUGUAUAAAAGCUGAAUAUUUAAGGAUCUCCUUUAUCAGGCACUGAGAUGCUUUGUAUACAUUACUUCAUUUAGUUUUCACAAUAGUCCUAAGAGGUGGAGGUAUUUUUGACCCUGUUUUAUAGUUGAAGAACAGGCUCAGUAAGGUUAUAUUACCUGCUCCAAAUUUCACAGCUAGUUAAUUUAGUUUAUGUUGGAAGUUAGCAUUUAAGGUUGGUUAUUUUUCCUAUGUGGCUCCAAUUGCUCCUAAAAUGGUGUUGAUUUUUCUGUUUAAAAUGAUCCAGAGGAGGUUCUUGGUUCAAAGCAGAUUUUUAAGUGAUUUAAAAGUGCCUCAUUGUCCCAGCGCCAAAUUAUCAAAGUUCAAGGAAUUAUGCAUUUACUCUAGAAGGCUACGGCUUUCAAAUAUUAACUGAGAAAGCCCUACUCUUAAUGAGCUCGUUAAUGCACAUGGCCGCCUUAGUGUUGCUGAACUCCGGUAACUUUCUUCUGCUUUUUUUCUGAAGACCUUUUAAUUCAGGGUGUGCAUUUUCCUCUUGCGUGUCACAAGUGCUAUUCAGGCUUUCUCUAGUUGAAUCCCCUGUUUGUGAGUGCAUACCUGCAGUAUUUUAUAUGCUAAGUGAAAUAUUUUUAAAUUUACGUUAGCACCUAGAUUAGCGUUGAACCUGUUUUAAGAAUGGUGAGUUCAUGAAAGGCACACUCUGUGAGAGCUAAAACUAGUUAUGUGGAGGUGAGAAAGUCUCAGCGUGUCUGAUCAGAGCAUCCAUUUCUGAGAGAGUCCAUCUGUGGGCAUAUCAUCAUACAAGAGAAUAAUGCCACCUUCAUCGAAGACCAUGAAAUACCAUGAAAUAUUCCAGGACUAGGCAUUGCUGACAGCCCCACAUCAUCACCUGCACCAUCUAGUUGACACAGAACACCUACCCACUUCCUUAAGCCACUCUAAAUCCUAACUGCUUUAAGUGACCUGAAUUCUUGAGCAUGUUGAAAGAACAUGCCAGUGUGAUGAUAAAACCACUUGGGAGUAAUCUUGGAAAAGUCAUGGAGAGGGGGAAGCAUGCCACAGAGUCCAUUUUCAAAAAUGGGGAAAUGGUAAAUUCGAAAACUUUAGAUUCAUAACUUACGUUGGUGUCUAGCAGAAUUGUAGAUCACAUUUUUUAAAAGAUUGGUCAGAAUCACUUACAAAAAUAAAAGUGAUGAUCAGUAUGUAGCGUAUGUUUGCUAAGAAUUAUUCAUGUCCAAUUAACCUCAUUUGUUUUUUAAUAAUGUUACUGGACAAGUAUAUCAGGGCAUUGCCAUAGAUAUGCAAUGUCUGCUUCAUCAGAACAUUUCGUUUUGUUAUGUUUUGAGACGGAGUCUCGCUCUGUCACCCAGGCUGGAGUGCAGUGGCGCGAUCUCAGCUCACUGCAAGCUCCGCCUCCCGGGUUGACGCCAUUCUCCUGCCUCAGCCUCCUGAAUAGCUGGGACUACAGGCGCCGGCAUCAGAGCAUUUAAUAACGUGCUACGUGUGUUCUUUACUCAAGAUGGAAAAAUAUGGAUUGGAUAGCGGUAUAGAUGAAUGAGUUUAGGUCUUUUACCCAAAGAGGGAUGAUCAGUGGCGUAAUGUCAGACUUGAGCAAGGUGUCGAUAGUGUCGCUUGAGAAAGGCAUAUGGUACAGCUGGUGGGAAAAACUUCACACAGUACAAGAGAUAGGGUAUUUGGAACCAAGGAGAUGAUAAUUGCGUCGUUCUUUGAAGCACUGUAGAUAGUGGUUACGAAUAGAGACUCCAAAGCCAGACUCUGGGCAAGUUAUUUGAGUUCUUUAUGCCUCUAUUUCUUCAUUCAUAAAAUACAAAUAAUAGUAAUAAUACCUACCUUAGAGGGCUGUUGAAGAUGUUGAAGGAUUAAAUUAUAUAAUCCAUGUAAAGUGCUUAAAGCAGAAUCGGAUAGUAAAUUGUAUAUAUUAGAUCCUAGUCUUCUGUUGUUGCUGCUGUUAACUACUGUCACUACUACUACUUCAGGCAAUAUUAUGCACAUUUCUGGGUUUGUGUUUAAACACAUAUCCAGAAUGUGGUAAAUAGGUUAGUUGUUGUUUUUUCAGGCAGAGUCUUGCUCUGUUGCCCAGGCUGGAGUGCAGCAUCAUGAUCUCGACUCACUGCAACCUCAAGCAGUCUUCCCACCUCAGCCUGCUGAGUAGCUGAGACUACAGGUGUGCCACCAUGCCUGGCUAAUUUUUUAAUAUUUUGCAGAGACAAGGUCUCACUGUGUUGCCUAGGUUGGUCUCGAACUCAAACUUGUGGACUCAAGCAAUGCUUCUACCUCAGCCUCUCAAAGUGCUGGGAUGACAGGUGUGAACCACUGUGCCUGGCUGUAAUUAGGUUUUGGAGAGUGUCUAGUAACUGUUAUUUGAACAGUGGUCCAAAAACAAUAGGCGUCUUCACCUUAGUGUAAAAGCUGAGAGACUUUCAAUCAGAUGAGGUCCACAGAAAAAAAAUUAAAAAAUUAAAAACUUUUAAGCUGAGAAAUGAUACUUUAUAUUUAUUUACUAUUACCAAUGUGGUAAAAGAGAGAUGGUCACAUUUUGAAGUCUGUACAUUUUGUCCAGUUUAAUAAGUGCUUUCUGUUAAGGAGCUAUAGUUUGGUGUAUGAGAAAUCUUCACUAAACUAGGUUUUAGGAGACCUCUUUCUUAUCUCCAGUCCAAAUCAGAUCAGUACAGUCUUCAACCAGUUGUUAUGAUCUUGGGUGAUUAGCUUAACUCAAUGGUUCUCUGCAGGGUGCAAUUUUAAACCCCCAGGGAAAAUUUGGUAUAUUUGGACACGUUUUUGAUUGUCACAGCUGGGGUUGGGGAGGUGUGCUAGUGGCACUUAGUGGAUACUGCCAUGGAUACUGCUAAACAUCCUACAGUGCACAGGACAGAGGCCCCACAGCAAAGAGUUAUCCUGUCCAAAAUGUCAGUAGUGUUAUGGUCGAGAAAUCCUGGCUUACAAGUUCAAUGUAUGUAUUUCUGUUUCUGACAUUUGAAUGCCAAUCUUUGCUUUAACGAAAUCACCAAGUAGCUUUAACAGUAUGUUUAUAAAAGGCCUUUGAGAGUUAAUGUAUGCUGAAAUCUGCAAGUGUAUACAGUGUACACAUUUUAUCAUCAGCAGCACGGUGAAAUAUUUGCUUUGUUUCCUGGAGGAAUAUAUUAUCGUGGUUUGAGAGUCAGAUACACCUUUGCUGGAAUCUCAGCCCUGCCAGUUUAACUUGCUGUGUGAUUUGGGGCAAGUUUCUUUAUCUGUGAAAACCAAAUCUCUAUUUCAUAGGGCUUAGAGGAAUAAACAAGAUAUACAUGUAAAUUAUGUAGCACAGUCCUUAGGCACAGUCACAAGAGAUAACUUUUUUUUUCAAAUUUACAUUUUCCAGGUUAAUAGAAUUGACUGAUGCUUUUUAAAAUGUAAGAUUUGGAAGGAGGAUAUAUAAGGAAGUUAGAUUUUUUAAUAGUUAAAAUAUUAAAAAUAAAAGGGCUCCUGUUUUCCAAAGGUGAUAAAUCUUAGGAGAAGUAAAUGUCUUUACAGAUAUCACUUUGGCCUUGUAGGGAAUGAAGAAUAUGCACUAAAGUGAGAAGCACUUAUUAGAGGGAGGCAUAAGUUGCAUGGAAAACAAGAGUCAUCUAUUUCUUAUCAGUCUGGAAUUAGCCAAUAAUAUAACUUCUGCAUUUGUGAAUUGUUCCACUAUAAAAACAUGUAAUGUUUGUUCUUAAGCAGUGUAAUUCUAUUUUUUAAUCUUACUCUUGAUAUUAUGUCUCUUAAAUAUGUUUUUCCAUGCCUUAAGGUGUAAGCAGCACACCUAGCAAAUGUAUGUGCAAAUGUGUCAAUUUUGUCAUCUUAGUGAUUUCUUAUACCCUCUCAGCCUUGCCUGAAAAGAUAAAGCUUUCAUGUGAUCACCCUUUCUGUCACUUCCACUUGUGUAUCAAGCAAGCUAUAGCAGUGUGUAGCUUAUCCGUAAGAGCCAUUGGCAUUGUAUGUAUUUGACUUAAUGGUGUGAAUUUUUGUAGGUGAUAGGGGUUGGAUGGGAAGAUUUCAGAGUAUUCACAAUCCGUCUGUUGUCUACCUUAUAAAGGCAGACUGUUUUGCAUUUCUGUUAAUUUUCCAGGGAGAUGGCAAUAAGAGGUCCAGCAAUGAAAAGUUCCAUGGCUUAGGAAGAGGCGCUUUUUCAGUUUGGAGAAUUGAAGUUAGGAAUUUUUUUGAAAAGUGGUCUUGAUUUUCUUUCUCAGUGUCCCUAUUGCAUUGAAUUGUGUAAACCUCACAUAAACAUGUGACUUGAAUCCUCUAGUGGAGUGAGUGUUAGUACCCUCUGCCCCCAGCAGCUUGCCUCUCUAUGGGUAUCUGGAAGGAAAUCUGUCCCCUCACAUCAUUGGGACAAUUCACAGCCAGCUCAUCCCUCUCAGGUGGUGGCUGCCCAAGGGGAGCACAGCAGUUCCAGCAUAAGGGGCAUGUGAAAUGUGACUGGCGCACAGAUGAAAACAUACUUCUCAGAAAUUACUAACAUAGACUAAGCCCUGCUAGUGCUUAGAGGCCUUCAUUAAGCUAACUUUCAAGUUUAAUUAACUUUCCUUAUCAUACAGAAGUAGACGGUGGUGUUCCAGACUCUGAUGGCCUCAAGCCGCCCCUGAGUUGCUGGGUAAGCAGUAUUGGCAAAGAAACCUGGUGAUCCUAACAGAGAAUCCUGAACUGGUGAUACAAAAUUGCAUAGUUCUAUGGGGUCAGAAGCGGAGAGUUUGAUACUCAAACCAAACUGAAAGUCAAGCUGAUAAUAAAUAAACUAAAAGAAAGACUAGGCAGUUUAAAAUUUCAGGUGGAACCAGUGACCACAAUUCUUGAGACCCCAUAAAACAAUUUAUCCACUUUAGGUGCAUUCUGUCACUUUGAUUUCUCAGAUAUGGAUGAGACUAGAAAUUACCACGCACUGCAGGAAGUGUUGCUGAAAAUGUUUGAAAGCUGAUUGUGUAUUUACAAGGCUCCUGGGCAUCAACUUGUAAUUUUGCAGUAAUUGGUACCAAAAUCCCAAGUUCUAGACUUGUGCUGAGUUAACAGAUGUAAAAAUAGAAUUGUUUUUUUCCCCCCUUUUGAAGCAAGGGUCUCACCAAAAGGCUCAAACACGUCCUAGACAUAAAGGAACAAACAGAUUUAAGUCAAGGUGGAGUGGAACAAUAUGCCUCAUUAUCCACACCAUAGGUCUAUUAGCUUGUAUUUUUUAAAGAGUUUAAGCUUGGCAUUCAAUGAAUUCUUUAAAUACAGAGUGUGGUUAUAGGUUUAUUCAUUUGUUUUUUCAAGAGGUCCCUCCUUCUUCCUUGAAAUUCCAAAGCUUUCAUUUCACUGGAAUUAUUGGCUUCUACCACGAGUAUGGUGUAUAUGCCAUACAUGAGGGCCCUCAGGUAAUAGUAUGUGUACUAUAUAUACCUUUCCCUCUUCUCAAUUUGGAAAGAAAGACCUGACUCCAAAAGAAAUUAUUAAACUAACCUAUAAUGAAUGUAUCACAGCAAACAUACAACAAGAGACCAUAACUUGGUUAUAGAACUAUAACUUGAUUAAAGGAACUAACAUGUUAUUCUGAGAGGGAAAUUGUCUGAAGAGGAAUUUAGAGAAGUAGAACUUGAAGACUGGGAUGGGAGACUGAAUUUGAGAGGCCAACUUGGCCUAGCUACAGAGAAGGUGCCUUACCCCUAGGGCGGCAUUACCAGGUCUCCAUAUGGGUCUUCCCCUAUGGUGGGGCUGUCUGAGGGCUUUUGAAAUCUGCCUAAGUUCCAAAUCUGAAUUAGAGAUUGGUCUUGCCCUCAUCGGUGAAUACCGCUGAGUCCUCCUUAACCUCACAGUGCACAGUGUCAGGCCACACAGGAAGACACAGAACAUAUUUUUGUUCCAUGCCCACUAUGCAUCCUUCUCAUGGUAAUUUGGCCACUUCAUGUAACUAUGCUUUUCAGAGAUCUGCCAUCAGACAUGCCAGCAAACAACCCACCUGAUGGUUUACAUUCUCACAAUAAGGUAUUCAGCUCGAGUUUUUACUUUAAUGUCACCACAAGUGUGGUCAGUAUGAAUGCUUUUCUGAUCAUUGUAUUUAUAAAUUUGCAAGACUAAAGGACAGCCUUGGACUAUGUGAGUCUCCCCAGAUAACACUGCACUCUAAGGACCAGCUGGCUUCCCCAGGUUUGCUUGUCUUCACCUUGAAUGCCCUUUCCUAUCUGACUUGCAACACAAGAGUGUCAUGACCAUCAUAAUAUUAUUAUCUUUUUUAUUGCAAUUUAGAAAACGUUGAGAAGAAAAAUGAAUGUCAUUGAGUGCUUAUUCAUGUGGGAAAUGUGGUGUUCUGUUCUGUGAGUGACUCAUGUAAACGAGUAAAAGAAACUAGAGUACAUUGUUAAAAUUACAAGGUAAACUAAUUCCUACUUUGCUAGUUAGUGUGUCCUAUAAUUCUCAUUUAAAUUGCACAGAUUACUAAACAACUACAGAAAUUUUCACCCAAAGCAGUUCAUAGACAAAAUUUCACAGAAUUUUUCAGUGUGAUUUUAUAUUGUUAAAAUUCUUGUAGACUUAUGAAAUAUACUUUCAUUUGGUUCUCAGGAUAAUAGGCUGUAUAUAGUUUCUUAGGCAUUUUGGGUUCCAGAGCCUGUGGUACUUUCCUAUAUAAUUGUCCUUUUUAUAUUCUUAUAUUCCCGUUGAUAUAUUGAAAGAGUUUCCUGAAGUUAUCUGUUCCUAUAUAAUUGUCCUCUUUAUAGUCUUAUAUUCCCGUUGAUAUAUCGAAAGAGUUUCCUGAAGUUAUCUAUUGCUAAUAUUUAGCAUUUACUUUUAGGAGCAAAAUUCUCAGGAGAAUUGAGAAAUCUGUUGUCAUUUAUUUUGAUUAUGUCCAAGUAAAGGUCAGAGAUAUGAAAUUAAAUGUUUGUAACUGACAAACUAGUCAUCACAGUCUACUUCAAAGGGAAUGUCUGUCACAGUUUCAGUAGUGCCAGGGUACAUAGAGAUAUGUUGUAUGAAAACCAUAUGGUCUUGGGAAGACUGUAGAGGAAUCCUUUUGGGAAAAGAGUAUGGAAUGGACAGGAACAGUUCAGGGAAUAAAUGGGAUUAUAUCCAGCGAGGUUGAAGAAUAGGAAAAACAGAAACAUCCAGUUAGAAUAAGUUUUUGUGUUUGAUAGCAGAGUAGGGUGACUAUAGUUAACAACAAUGUAUUGUAUAUUUUGAUGUAGCUAGGUGAGAGGACUUGAAAUGUUCCCAGCACAUGGAAAUAAUAAAUACUGGAGGUCAUGGAUAUCUCAAAUACUUUGAGUUGAUCAUCACAGUCUAUGCAUGCAAAAACUAUCACAUGUACCCCAUAAAUAUGUGCAAAUAUUGUGUAUCAAUAAAAUAAAAAGAAAAGGAAAAAUAAAGCAAUAAUUCUAACAUUACCUCUUUCCAAAGUGAGUGCCUCUCACUACUGGGUCUGGACUCUAAUCUAUAUGAAUAAAAUGAAUGGAUUUUAUUCCCUAAGAAUUUGUUAACUAAGUUAUCUGAGUAAGUUAUAUGUCCAUGUUUGUAGCCAGUAGCAGGAGGGAGGUCAGGCAGGCUAGGGGUUGUUAUAAUCUUUUUUUGUUUUGUUUUGUUUUGAGAUAGAGUCUCGCUCUGUCAGCCAUGCUGGAGUGCGAUGGUACAAUCAUGGCUUACUGCAGCAUGAACUCCCAAGCUCAAAUGAUUCUCCUGCCUCAACUGCCCCCCCGACCCAAUAGCUGGGAUACUUGAGACGCACCCCAGUAGCUGGGACUACAGGCAUGCACCACCAUGCCCUGCUAUUUUUUUUUUAAAUGGAGUCUCACUCUGUCACCCAGGCUGAAGUACAGUGGUGUGAUCUCAGCUCACUGCAACCUCUGCCUCCCAGGUUCAAGCGAUUCUCCUGCCUCAGCCUCCUGAGUAGCUGGGACUACAGGUGCGUGCCACCACACCCAGCUAAUUUUUUGUAUUUUUAGUAGAGAUGGGGUUUCACCGUGUUAGCCAGGAGCCUCGCUAAUUAAAAAAAGUUUUUAUUUUGUUUUUUUUUUUUUUUUUUUUUUUUAAGAGAUGAGGUCUCAGUAUAUUGCCCAGGCUGGUCUCUGGGCUCAAUCAUUCCUUCUACCUUUGCCUCCCAGAGUAUUGGGAUUACAGGCGUGAGCCACUGCACCUGCCAGUUAUAAUGUUUUUAAACUGUGACUAGAAUGAAUAAAAGGGCUAGUAUUUCUAUGUUGCUUUUCUCUAUACCUACUUGUUCCCUGCCAAAGCAUACAAGAACACCACCAGCAGCAGAAGGCCUUCCUCAGAUUACAGAGGACCAUAUGCCAGACCUUUGAUGUCCAAUACAAUAGGCACUAGCCACAUGCGAAUAUUUAAAUUAAUAAUCUUAGUUGGACCUAACACAUUUCAAGUGCUCAAUAGCUACAUAUGUGGUUAGUGGCUAUCAUAUUAUGUAGAACAGAUACAGAACCAUUCCAUCAUCUCAGAAAGCUCUACUGGACAGCACUGUGCUAUAUACACUGUCUAAAGGAAGCUUUUUUUAAAUGAAUUUUUUGAUAUUUAGAUACAAAUUUAGGGAAAAUGAUUCAGCCAAAAGUUCAGCCUUAAAAAAAAUAGAUAUUAAGGCGCUGGAUCCAUUUUCAAGCAAGUCCUCUAUAAAUCAAAAUAUUUCAGGGGUUUAACUGGCUCUUUUAGGCCAAACAAAGGUAUAUUAUUUUAGUUUUCCUCAGGUUUAAACUUUGAAUCCUAGAAGUACAUGAUGGCUUUCAAGAGUAGACACAGUGAAUCUUUAGCAUGUGUAUAGGCACCCAUUCUAUUGUAACUGGUUAGUCAGAGCUUAGCAGGGGGAAAAAAAAGCCACUCUUAUUUACGGCGGGGGGAAUGCGGUAAAGUUACUUCCACAGGUGAUGCAAUGGCAGGAAGUCAUUACCAACCCCAGGUUGAAGGGACAAUUGGAGGAGGCCGUUUGGAGGUCAGGGUGGAUAGGAGCUGAGACCAGAAAGGAUAUCAAAGAUAUCAACAGAAAAUAAGGUGAGAAGUGCUCCUGGUGGCUUCUCCCUUUCUCGGGUUAGGCAGACAGAAUUCUUAUACAGAAAUUGUAGAAAUACAGAAUUUCUAUACAGAAAAUGUAGUACUUCAUCAUUUUCCUUAGAAUGCUCACAUUUUUGUGGUUUUAUUACCUGUGCUAUUCAUAGUGACAUCACUAGGGGACUUUUGAGGAUUAACCACUUCUUCACCUAGAUUUUUAUCGGCACAUUCUAUGAUAUAUCACUUAGCAAAUCCAGAGAGGUUAAACAGUUUAAGCCAUGAUAGGGACAGAACUGGAAAAAUGCUAAUUCUUGCUCUUUUACUUGUGCACGUUGCCACUGGGCCUACUGCAGAAAUGCUACUAGUAAAGGGAGUAUAUCAUCAGUUCAGUCUGGGAGCAGAAACUGCAUAGUAGUUUAAACAAGGAAAGUUUAAUAUUAAGACUUAUUAGGGCCAGGUGAGGUAGUUCAUACCUGUAAUCCCAGCACUGCUUUGGGAGGCCAAGGCAGGAAGAUUACUUGAGGCCAGGAGCGCAGGACCUGCCUGGGCAACAUAGCAAGACACUGUCUCUAUAAAAACAAACAAACAAACAAAAAAAUUACCUAGGUGUGGUGAUGCAUGCCUGUAGCCCUAGCUGCCUGGGAGGCUGAGGUGGGAGUGUCUCUUAAGCCCAAGGGGACAAGGCUGCAGUGAGCUAGGAUCACACCACUGCACUCCAGCCUGGGUGAUAGAGGAAGACCCUAUCUCUGAAGAAAAAAAAAAAAAGAAUUAUAGCUAUAACAAAGGAUUGGAGCAAUGAUAAGAUUGGCUAAUAAAAAGUAAACAGAACUCUAUAGAAAUAGCAGAUAUAGGUAGCAUCUACUACUCCAAUGGCUGAGAUAGAGGAUCCAAGGAAGAGACCAACUUCCUACCCCCUCUCAGAGCUGAGAUCCAGACCUUGUUGGAGAGGACACGUCCUUGAUUCACUGCAUGGCAGAGCAGUUGCUGUAGUGCCACACCAGCAAAACUUACUAAAAAUCUGCCUUCCAGAACUUGCUGAAAAUCCAUCCUUCAUGGUCCCAGGGAAAGCUAUUCAUGGGCGGAUAUCUACUGGAGGCACUCUGCUAAAAACUGUUUGAGACAGGCUUUGGAGAAGCUGCACAUCCGACAGGAGUCUGAUGUGACUCCUGAUCAGACCAGGAAGCAAAACUCCUUCCUACAAUGUCUCUCUAGCAUUUUCUACAGACAAAAAUUAACAAACAUCAUGUCAGCUAGCAAAUGGAAAAUACUUACAGGGCUCAGAUCCCCUUUUGCAAAUCAGGCUGUAAAUGGUGAAUUUGUAGCUGAGAGGCAGUAAAUUGAUAACUGACACAGGGAGAAAAACAAGACCACCCUUCUUCUCAGAGCCUUUAUUAUUAUUUUUUUCAACAAGGUAAUUGCACAUGUAUGUGUAUGUGUGUGUGUAUAUAUAUAUUUAGGUGGGGUUUUCCUUCCAGUAGUACUUCAUCAUUUUCCUUAGAAUGCUCACAUUUUUGUGGUUUUAUUACCUGUGCUAUUCAUAGUGACAUCACUAGGGGACUUUUGAGGAUUAAGUAUUUUAGUUUUACUGUUCAUCUCUUAAACCUUGGAUAAAUACAUGAAUAUUAAUGAGUUGGAGCCACAUUUUUGAAAUGACAUUCAGCUAAAUGACAUUCCAGGCUUUUGUUUAAUGCCUAUGAAGAUAUGUAGCAUAACCUAGAAUUAUAGUUGCAUGUGAAAUAAUUCAAUUUGGGAUUUUAUCUCAAGAAUUAUAAAUAUUUGCCAAAAGAUUUCAUAAUACAUUCUAGUAUAUUUUAUUUGUACAUGGUAGGAUUUUUCUUUCAUUUGUGAGGGUGUUUCUUUACUGCUUUUCAUGAAUUGGGAUAGUUCUUCCAGAAGAGCUUUUCAAAGAUUUUUCUUCUCAGUUGUUUUCCACAUUCUACAACUGUAAACUGCUAAUUUUUUGUGGCUUCUUGCUCUAUACACCAUGCAAUGCAUAAUUUAUCAGUUUGUUUAAAACAUUAGAAAGGGAGAAAUACUCAGCCUUGUCCUUGAACCUGAGUUGAUACUCGAUCUAUCUCCAUCUGCAUUGCCCCCUUUUUCUCUACUUUGUCUCUUAUUUUGCUGUAUUUUUUCUUCCUCAGAACUCUCCUGAAAAGCCUUUGAUUUGGUAAAUAUAUUUUGGGAUUUUCAGAUGUUGAGGUUUAUUAUAAAUGCUUUAAAUUUUCUGGUUUUAUUUUUUUUAAUUAGGUUUUGUUGAGGAACAGAGUGUAAAAGAAAGGAUAUGGUUAAAAUAUGAAAAUAAGUAAAAAUGGUGCAUGUACAUCGUUAGUAUACAAAUGAUAUCAAAUAGUUUAGAAAGAGAUGUCAAAGGCUCCUCUCACUGUAACUGUUAUUACAUUUCUUGUGAUUUGUUCCAGGAAAAAAAAAUACAUAUUUUGGCACAUAUCUGCGUCUAUCUUGCUUUUGGCUUUUUACAUUUUUAAUAAAGGGAUUAAUAUACAUACCGUUCCUUAGCUUUUUCUUUGUACUUUACCUAUUUUUGAGAUAUAUUCCUGUCAACACAUACAGAUCUUCUUUAUUCACUUUAAUGAUGGUACAAUAUUUUAUUUUAUGGGUGUAUAAUAAUUGAUUUUAUUUUUGCCUUUUUUCUGGAUGUUUUAAUAGUUGCCAUUGGGGGGAUUGUGUUUAGCUAUUGGAUUUAUUGCAGUCUGCCUUUCUGUAAAUAUUUUCGUAUAAAUAUCUUGCUGACAUACCUGUAGGGUAAAUUCCUGUGAGUGGGAUUGCUACAUCAGUGGGAAAAUACAUUUCAAAUUUUGAUAAACAUCACCAAAUUCUUCUCUGGAAAGGUCACUGAUUGUUUGUUUUUUCGAGACAGGGUCUCGCUCUUCACCCAGACUGCAAUGCAGUGGCACAAUCAUAGCUUAUUGCAACCUCAAACUCGUGGGCUCAAGCAAUGCUCGCUCCUCCCAAGUAGCUAGGACCACAGGCAUGCACCACGAUGCCCACCUAGUUUUUUGUAUUUUCUAUAGAGAUGGGGGUCUCACUGUGUUUCUCAAGCUGGUCACAUACUCUUGGCCUCAGGCAGUUCUCCCACAUCAGACUCUCAAAGCACUGGGCUUACAGCUGUGAGCCUGGCCUUUUUAAAAAAAAAAAAAAAAUCAAAACAAAACAAAACAAGAUUAUGUCUUUCCCACGCUUCCAUCAACAUUUUUCAUUCACCAAGUUUUAACAUUUUUGCCAAUCUGGUAAGUUAAAAAUUUACUUUCCCUCUGGGUGAGGAUCUUUUCAUAGGUCCAUUGUGAGUUUCUUUCUGUAAACUGCUCACUCAUGUGCUUUCUUCUUCCUCUUUCUCCCUCUUUUUCCUUCCUUUUGCCCUUGUGUCUUCUUGUCUUUAUCAUAUUGACUUGUAUGAGCUCAUUUUAAAUUAGGAAAAUUCAUCCUAUUUCAUAUGUAUUAUACCUGUUUCCCCCAUGUUACCGUCUAUCUUUUGAUUUCCAUUAAAAAGAUUUUUAUUUUGGUGUAAGGAAUAUUAAACAUGUUCUUUUACAAAGGAAAUAAAAGAAGGGUAGGGGUUGAGGAAAUCUGGCCAUACUUUCUGCUGUUUUUGUGGCCUGAGUAGUUGUAGUUUGGGGCUAAAGGUUAUCCCACCUGACACUACCAUGUCCCAUACCUGUGGAGACCCUGUACUAUCUUACAGCAAAAUUAUUCUUAAGACAUACUAGAUGUUGGUGUCCUUCCCCUCUGUAUUUGCCUAAACCUUCAUCAGUGUAUUGAGCCUCUUAAGAGCAGGUGAGCUUAUGAACAACCUUGUCUGGAAACGUCAGAAUUUAGCCACAUGAUGAGAUCAUUCCUGGUAGCCAGGAGUUGUAGAUAAUGCUCACUUCUGUAUCCUGAGCACCUAGGGUAGCAUCUGGCUUUUGAAACACCAUGUGUUGAAUGAAUGAAUGAAGACAAAGAAGAGCAAGAGCAGAGGAUGAGCAGAAAUAGAGAACUCGAAUGAAGAUUCACUUUGGAACACAUUAGUCAAUUAGAUAUAUGCAUGCCUGACAAAUGUACCCCUAGAGUCUAGAAUACUUUCAUUUCUUAUCUUCGUAACCUCUACUCAGGCUCUUGACAGCUGGGAUGGGUUUAAGCUAAUAGUAUAUUAUUUACCUCAUAAACUUUAUGGAACAUUGAACAUGCGAACCGUGUACUUGUGCCAACUGUUAGUUAGUUGAAACUCUUCUUUCUUUGAAUUUACGUAAUUUUCUGUCUAGACUGGCCAGUGAGUAAUAAUCAUGUCUGUUCUUUUGUGAGUAGUGUUAUUAAAACUAUGUUUUUCGGAUUUUAAGAUAAUAGAUCAAAAAUGAAUUUCUGUCUAAAUUUAUUCAAAGAACAAACUUCUUCGAACAUUUAAAAUGGUUCUGGUUACAACAUAAUGUCUUUGGCAGCAACUUGGGUGGAACUGGGGGCCAUUAUUCUAAGUGGAGUAACUCAGGAACGGAAAGCCAAAUACUGCAUGUUCUCACAUAUAAGUGGGAGCUAAAUUAUAGGUACACAGGGACGUACAGAGUGGUAUAAUGGACAUUGGAGACUCAGAAGGGAGGAAGGUAAUGGAUAAAAAACUACCUAUGGGGUACAGGGUACACUGCUCUGGUGACAGGUACGCUAAUAUCCCAGACUUCACUAUACAAAUCAUCCAUCUAACCAAAAACCACUUCUACCUCUAAAGCUAUUGAAAUUAAAAAAAAAAAAUGGUUCUGGUUAACAAAAAUUGAGUAUACAAAUGGCUUGUUACAUACUAUGUAAACUAUGACUCAACCUAAAUCCUAGAAAAAUAGUUGACUAGUUCUUUGUUUAAUUAAACAUCUCCAGAGAAGGUUUUUAAAGAUUUCCUCACAAUUCAAAUAAUCUAUAUACUUAUUCAUACAUAUGGAAAGUCUUUUAAUGAUAUCCUAUGAAGGGCAAUACUGUGCAGUAUUUUCUUGGCUUGGCAUGUAAUGUUAUACCCUGAAAAUGUCAAUAAAUCUUAAUUUCCAGUAGGAUCGUGGCCCCUUUUUCUUGCCAUUUGACCUGAGAUGUCUAAUGGUUUUGUUUAUUCUUCAUAGUUUUAUGGAGGCAAUUGACUCCAUUAAUUUGAAUUUACUGAAAUAAAAGCCAACAAUAGGAAGAUAGAUUAAUUUUUGAAAAAGCUAAUGCUAAGCUUUGACUUCUGUUACUGUUCAGUGGCAUUCAAUGCAAAAAUAAUUGAACCUCAGAACAUUAGAGAAAUAGUCAUUGUUGUUUUGAGUGAUCAUGAUGCUUAUUACGCAUCCAUUUCAAUGCGGACUGAUGCAGUAAUUGAUGGAUGAUGCCAUUAAUUAGGCUUUUGACCAGACAAAUUUAUUGUAGUUUGGUAAUUUUUUAGGCAGAAUAUUGAAAUGAAAGGUAAAUGGAGAUUUUUUUAACAAAAUGAAGAUGUUUAAAAUGUCAACAGAAAGCUCACAAAUAAUUUCUUGGGUACAACAGUUUUGUACCACUUUGGUCCAUCUUUUGCAUCUUUAGCUUAAUCUUAAAAAAUCAAGGUGACUAAGUAAGGUGACAGAAAUUCAUUUGUGAAUUUGUCUUUGACAUUUUGUGCAGGAGCAUAAAUGAAUACGACAAGGGAAUCUACUUUGAAAAAUGAGUGUUUGAAAGUAGGUGUUUCUUGGAUUUUUUUAGCCUCAGUGAGGACAGAUCUGUGGGUGAGACCUUGGUGCUUUGUUGAAAACCAGUUGGCAUUGAAGAAGGCAAAUGAAAAAUAGAAGCCUAAUGUUGAUUGUGACAAAUGUAAAACAUGUAUCCCUUAAGAAAAUUUCAGGAGCUUUUGGUGGGGGGUAUUUCUGGUUGGUUGGUGUAAAGUUUUGGUGGCAUAUAGACCUUUUGAAGGAGUACUUUAUAGUUGGAAUAGAGUGUGAACCACCUGAGAAUCAAACUAGAGGGAUUUCUCCUGUGGGUGGAAAAGCAGAGGCUUUGAAAAUGAAUGCUUCUGUGUUUGGUUCCCAGUGUUGCCACUCACUGAGGGAUCCCAGUAAGGAACAAACUCUCUCCGAGCCUCAGUAUUCUUAAUUUGCACAAGUGGAGAUUAAAAUGUCUCCAUCAAAGAGUUUUUAAAGAAUAGGUAAAUUUGGCACAUAGUAAUCACUCAACAAAUGUGUUAUUUUUAAAGAAAGAGUUUCUAGUAUUGUUCAGAUUAAGAGGGUGGCCACUGAAAAAUAUUUUCAGGACUACCAAAGGUUAAUAAAAUAAUUACAGUAUAAGGUAUGGAAAUUGGGGCUAGUUUAGAACUUGCUGUUUUUCAGCAAGGCAGAAAUUUGCUGUGUAUUAUUAGAAUGUGACAAUUAAUGAUUUUUCCCAUGGCUGGCUCAAGUGUCAGAUAAUUGACCCUGGUUUACGUCGUAUGUCUCAAGAUGAGGCCACAAGUCCCAUUGAGGUCAAUUACUAGGCAUAAGUGUUUAUUUCAAACAGUUUGUGUCUCUGCCAUUGGUCUGGUCACACACACUAAUUAUCAUCAUCUUGAGGCAUUGCAGUUGCCUGGUUGAGUGGAGGCACUUGGGAGCUUCCUGCCCAGGAACCCUCCGGCCUUGAUGUGGUCUAUUGGGAAAUUGGUUACAUCAGUAUUGGCCAUAAGACAGGAUCUGACAACUGUCCAGACUUUCAUUAUUGCCUGAUACAUUCUGGUCACAUACUGAUAUUGAACAGGUAGUAAAGGAACAGUCAGCACUUGUGGUUUUGUACUUCUUACCUUUUUCCUCACAAAAAUAAAGCUGCUUUCAUAUUUUCUUCUUACUAAUAAGAUAGUGAGCAACCUGGGCAACAUAGCAAGACCUUGUCUGUAAAAAAAUUUUUUUUUAAUUGGCUGGGCGAGGUGGUAUAUAGCUGUAGUCUCAGCUACUCAGGAGGCUGAGGUGGGAGGAUUGCUUGAGUCCAAGAGUUCGAGGCUGAAGUGAGCAGUGAUUAUACCACUGCAUUGCAGCCUGGGUGACAGAGCGAGAACCUUGUCUCUUAAAAAAAAUAGCUAUAUAUAUAUAUAUAUAUAUAUAUAUAUAUAUAUAUAUAUAUAUAUAUAUAUAUAUGCCAGGAUGUGUUCUAUAGGUCUUGUGUUUAUAUUUUGUUGAUCUUCACAAGCUAUGGUGUAGGUGCUAUUGUUAUCCUCAAUUUGCAGAGGCAAAAAACUGCAUCACAGAGUGGGUGAGUAAUUUAUUCAAGGUCUCACAGCAAGUAAACAGAAGAGCUAGGUUUUAAAUCUAGGCCAUCUGGCUCCAGAAUCUUUUGACAACUGUACUAACCUUCCUCUCCAUUAGAAAGUAUAGACAGUUAUACUGAAUAUAUAUGAAAAGAACAUGAACAACCAUGUAAAACCCAUCUAACCAGUGAAAACCAUUCCUAGCACCUCACGCACGUACUUCCAGAUUCCUUCCUUGAACUCUUUUUUUUUUUUUUUGAGAAGGAGUCUCACUGUGUCGCCCAGGCUGGAGUGCAGUGGCGCGAUCCCGGCUCACUGCAAGCUCUGCCUCCUAGGUUCAUGCCAUUUUCCUGCCUCAGCCUCCCGAGUGGCUGGGACUACAGGCGCCCACCACCAUGCCUGGCUAAUUUUUUUAUAUUUUUAGUAGAGACAGGGUUUCACCGUGUUAGCCAGAAUGGUCUCGAUCUCCUGACCUCGUGAUCCGCCUGCCUCGGCCUCCCAAAGUGCUGGGAUUACAGGUGUGAGCCGCCGUGCCUGGCCUCCUUCCUUGAACUCUGAUGGGAAGUUCUCUCCCCCUGACCCUUUUCUACUUCCAAGAGCUAAGCAUAAUGAACAAUCUGGUAUAUAUCUUCCCAAAUAUAGAUGCAGUUAUUCACAUUGUACAUAUAUAGGUAAUUCAUACACAUUCUCAUAUAUCCUCCUGUGUGCAUUGUUCUGCUAAGCACUUUUUCUCACUCAGUAUGUCCUGGAAAUAUUUCUGUAUGUGUCAUUGUAUAUAAUUUAACACAUUCUUAAACUGACUGCUUAUAUGGACUGCACCACUUCUGUAGGAUGGGUGUACUAUAAUUUCAGUGCACCACUUUCAUUGAUGGACAUUUACAUUGUUGUCAUAUUUUUUCUAUAUUAUUUUCAAUAGUUGCAUAUUCUAUAUUAUUUUCAAUAGUUGCAUACCUUUUAUUGUAUGAAAGUACUAUAAUCUCCUGUUUUGAAAUUCAGAUUAUUAGAAGGUACAGGGAUGAAUAUUCUCAAAACUUGGAAUUUGAGCACAUCCUUCCUUAGUUACCUCCCAGUCCCAAUUAAAAUGCUAAGUCCAAAUGAUCACCUUGUCAUUUAAAAAACCAACUUACUGCGGUAUAUUUUCUAUAUAAUUCAGUGAUUUUCAGUAAAUUUACUGAGUUCUACAACCAGCACCAUAAACCAGUUUUAGAACAUUUCCAUCGGUUCUUAAAAGAUAAGAUUCCUCUCUUAUCUUUUUACAUUUAAUCUCUACUUCCACACCGAGCCCUAGGCAACUACUAAUCUACUUUCUGUCUCUAAAGUGUUUCCGGUCCUGGACAUUUCAUAUAACCUGUCACUUUUAAGAAUUUGAUAUCCAUAAGUAGUAUUUCUUUUCUUACUCUUUUGAAUAAUUUGGCCUAUAUACAACUCCUAGCUAGAACUGUCUAUUAUAUUAGGGUACUGUCUUGAAUAAUAAUAAUAAUAUAUAUAUUUUUUCCAUUCCAUAGAGACAAACUGCUUCUCUGUUUAUAAGGCUUCUUUGGUAAUACUUGCCAUAUUACAAGAGAACUGUUAAGCUUGUUUGGUUAAUUUCUUCAUGUGGUGGCUUGAUAGUAAUUGUUAUUCUUGGCUUGGUUUGAUUGAGAACUGAAUAUGCAUUGAUUUCUCAGAAGACUUGCUACCAAAAUAUAGCAAAAACUUACCAGAACCUCCCCCCAUGAGAAGUAACACUGAAAAGUUCUCACUUAUGACAUCACAUCCCAACUUACAACACCGGUAUUGUUAGCUUCAAAUUGCUUACAAACGUUCUGCAAUUCUUUUGGAUUAAGUAACUCUGUACUAUUAAAAUAAUUUUUAAAAUAUUAUUUUAUUGCCUUUAUAAACCAGUUUGGAUUAAAAGCUAAUAUUUUUUAAAGGUUAGGAUAAUUUCAUUUCAUUAUUUAAUAUUUCAAAAUCUGAUGAUAUGAUCAUAUUUUGAAGUCAUCUGAUAGUUCCUGAAAGUAUUUUAGAUGUCUACUCCCUGCAUUUAUACAUCUGUUUAGAGCCUGAUUGUUUUUAUAUGGUGUGCUUAUUUAUUUUUUGUCAUUGCACGUGAAUAAUUACUGUUUUCUGAAGACCUCUACUUUUUAAGAAGCUCCGAGAGAGUGGAAAAAUAACCACCAAACUUGUCUGCCUCACUUUAUUACUGAGAGAAAAAAUUUGCAGAAUGAUAUUAACUAUAUACUAAAAUCUUAGCACACCAGAGUACAAAGUCAGGGACGGAAAACUUUCUGUGUGUAGCCUUUUGAAAUGUAUCUAUAAGUAGAAGGCAUUCCCAAGUCACAUGCUGAAGAGCGGCGAAAUGGCUUAGAGGCAGAGUUCUUAGGUGCCACUCUACCUAUUUCAGGCAGAUUCUGUCACCAUCAGCCCUUCGUAGGUCACAUAACUUACUUGAUUUUAGUGACUUAUUUAAAAUCAGUAAUUAACACCUCAAGAGGAAAAAGCUUUUCUUUAGAAGAAAUAACAGAUUUAUCUUCAAUACCUCUGAAACCUAAAUGGUUGCUUAAGUAACAGCUGUUGCAUUUUAUCAUCAUUGGCAAACGGGAAAGGCAGCUUCCUCAACUUGUGUUUGUCUUCUAAAGGAAAAACCAAAGCAAUAUAUAGCAACUGAUGCUUAUCCAGAAGAGAUAACUCAGAUGCACAGAGGCAAAGAGAUGUGGACAUCUAAAUAAACCCAGACACUUUGUUCUUCAGAACUUUUAAACAUAGGCAUUUUCUCUCUCGGCGAGAGAGUGAGCUGUGAUCAGUUGUGUGUGUAGCCAGGAUGUUGCUAAAGCAAACUGACUUUAUCUGCCUUGCACGCCUUCUCCUCUGCUUUGGUGUCAUGCCUGUCUCCUUUCUAAGACCAGCUAACCAUACUUGGUUUCUUCUGUCCUCUUUAACAUCUUCAUCUUGCUUUAUUGUGCAUGUGUAUGAUUUGAGGUUCUAGAUCCUUGAACUGGGGAGUGACAACUUAGACACCCACAGAGACCACGUAUCUAUCCUACCUGGUCCUGCAGAGUGCCCUACACUGAGUGAGUCCUCUGUCUAAGAGUGCUGCUAACCAUCUCCUCAAGGGCAGUUAUCUGCCAUUUGCAAAGAAUGUACAAGUUCUCUAAAUCUAGCAACUACAUCAGAGAUCUUAGAUGAUGAUUCAUUUGAAGAGAAUGGGUUGGGAGUACUCAUGCAAAGAGAAGAAGCAUUUUUUUUUUGCUUUUGAUCUUACUGCACAUUAAUUUUGAGUAAAUUUGAUAGUACAAAUCAACCAACGGAUAUUCACAUUUUGAGUGUCCCGUACUUGAGCUCCUGAGAGUGUGCAGAAGGGUGGAGUGCUUAUCUUCAAGUAACACCGCCGGUUCACCACACAGCUUUCUUUUUAACAGAACACUGGAGGCUGCCGCUGUUGGGAUGCAUUGAGGGGAGGGGACCUAGCUACUUUUAAAAGAAUCUUUGGGUAUAGAAAUUGGGGGAAGGAAGAUGUGAAAAAUAAUGCCACUUGUGGGUGGGGUGGGGAUGGAUGUGAGAAGACAGACUGCUAAAAGCAGCCAUGAUUGGUGAGCACCUGCUGUGUGCCUAGACUCUACUAGGUACUCUGCAGCUCAUUAUCUCAUUUAAUCCUGUGAGUCAGGUGAUGGUAUCCAUAUUUUUAUAGACAGGGAAACUGGCUUGGAAAGGUCAACACUUCCUCAAACAAACAAACAAAAACAGAUGGAGUUAGUCUAAUUCUUUCUAUUUGUAACUAAUUCGUCUUAAGAUUAACAUGUUCCUUCCUCUCUCUAGUUCCAAAAUAUCCCCCCUUCCACGGUCCUGAAUUUUUUCACUUCUCUUUUGUAUACUCUUGAACUGGAGGCAUUUACAGUUGUGGAACAUAGACCUUCUGAAAUGCAAAACAUCCUAGGGAAGAGAAAUGUACCUUACUGUGUGGGUUGACUUUUGCCUUGCUUUGCUCAACUCCUAGCUGAGAAUACCUGGACUUAAGAUAAUGGGGGCUGCACGUGGGAAGUAAAGAGAGGAGAAGAGGUAGUCUUUAAGCUUGGACCUCUAGAGGGGUGGGACUGGGAGCCCCACCCUGAGGGCUCAGAGAAGCAAAGACUCCUGAGGAGACAGCCACUAAAAGGAGGGCAAGAUUUCACCAAAGGCUAACUUUUCCCCUUCUGGUUUUGUUAACGUUUUUCAUCAUGGAAAGGGAGGAAAUGCACUGGAGGGUCCAGACCUUGGUUUAGUUCCUCUUUCAGUAGAAUUGGGAUCCUCAGAUGAAUGAUGAAUCGGUUAAGGGUGGAAAUAACUUUUUCAGCAGUAUACAUACCCACCAUAAACAUUUUAUUAACUUUAGAAACAGAAAUGUUUAGGAUUUCUCAAUGUUUUAUGUAGUGUCAAGGAAUUUUCUUUUGAAUAUGGGUCCUCUGAUUUGUGCCAUUUCUUGUCUUUCCUGCACAAGCCCCACCCAUAAUCCUUCAUCGAUGUCCAGUCUUUAUUUCUUUAAAGUGAUGCCGGAACAUCAAAACUUCAAAGCAGCCCAAUACUGAAUCCUUCCACAUUUUAAGUUACAUUUUCCUCGUAAGAAUAUUAAAGUUGUCUCAACCACCUCUAAUUUUGCAGCAAUCUUUUGGUAAGACUGUUUACCUUUAUCAAGUCUUUCUAAAGCAUUCAAUUUAGUUUUGUGGAAAUAACAGCUCACUUUCUUUCCAGACUCCAGUUUCAUUGAUUACUCAAUAUUUAUUUAAAUUAUGUAAUAAUGGAAACAAGCAGGUUUGGAGACAAAUACAGUGAGUCUUGGUAAGCAUUGCAUAUUGACUAAUGGGAGCAGAGUUGCCAAGCUUAGGUUGGCUAAUACUAAUGACAGCGGGCAGUUGCUUAAUCAUCCACAUGCAUCAGUAUGUCUGAGUGAGGGGUAACUAAUCCAGUGUGAGAGUCAAGUAGAAUUGUUUAAGAGCACUUUAACUGUAGUCAAAUGCUACACCUGCUCCUUAAUAGCUUGAAGGAGCUAUUUAUUACAGGGAUCCCAACAACUCGUGUGAUUUGAUUUUUACUAUGAGUUGCACCUAGAAUUGUAAACAUUCAAUAUACUAAUCAUAACAGCGACCAUGAAGGUGUUUUUUUUCUUGGGGAGGUGUCUAAUCACACACACACAAAAUCAGUAUGAUCAGAGAGGGCAGGAAAUUGAUUUAUCACCCUCAGGGGCUUGAUGUUGCUCUUGUUAAAGGGACAAGCUUGUUAGAUGUGAGCUCACGCAAAGUAUUGCCAGAGAUCUCCUGCCAAGCUCUUCCUGUUAUGUAAAAGCAAAAAGGAGUGGGCAGAUUAUGAAAUUAUUCUGUAUAUGAUGAUUAGUUCGUGAUGGUAUAGUGAUUUGUUAAUCUGGUUCAUUACUUUAAAAAGCUUAAUCAUAGUCAUCAACUUCCAUAUUUUUACUUUUUAGAUAGGCAGAAAGAAUUCAGACCAGUUAUUAGUUGCUAAACAAUUUGUUGUUGAAUGAAAAGCAAAAUCCUGGAAAAAAACAACUUAGAGUAUUAGGGUCUAACAGCCUGAAAGUCAUUGUAAACUUGACUUGUUUUUCUGCCCCUGAAAUUAAGUUAGAUGAAUUAAAACAAAAGGCAAAGGCAGUUAUUUAAAAAACUUGUUUUUGCUAUUGCAUAUUUAUUUCAUAUAACCUCAGAUUUAUUUUGAUUUCCAUUUCUUGGUGCCUGGCACCAGAAUUUGUGCAGAUCUAUUUCAAAACCACACAUUGUAAAAUCAACACUAUUGACAGUUAUGGGUAAUUGAAUGGCAAAUGGGGUUUCCAACUGGGUGCUCCAACUGGGACUCUUAAACAAGGCUUGACAAAUUCUGCUUUGUCAGGUGUCAUAAAAUAUGGUUCAGAACGCAUCUGUAGUGUCAAGGGAAAAUCACUUAUGCCAUUCCCUGUAUUACCACUUCUGACUCUUGUCCGUCCUGAAGUAGGAAUUCACAUGGCUUAUGAUGGAGUCUUUGUUUUAGGAAACACGACACAAACGCUAAGACUCUUCAGAUAUCAUCACUGAAUCUUUAAGUUCAAUCCAGUUGCUAGAUUUGGCCUGUAACAUUUGGCUCAGGGAUUCCUGGUGGCCAAAGGAAAACAUCACAAGAGUCACAUUAUCUGUAAGAUAGGAACAGACUAGUUGUUUUAAAGAAAACUUCUCUUAAAACUCAAAGCAGAAAGAUGUCAGAAUGGGAUUUAAGUAAUUUCUGCCUUCAGCCUAGGGAAUUGGCUUGUAUGGCAGUUUUUUCCACUCCUUUUGUGGUAUCUAUAUAGAGAUAGGAUAUAUGACUCACUUGGCAAAGGUCAGGAGUCUGAACAUUUGGGUAAUGAGUACCUUGUCCUAGGAAGAUAAACUGAGCACAGUGUCCCUAGGACUUGCACGAUCGAAGAAUCCCCUUGGUUGGGGCUUGGACCUUUGCCAGCUCAUCUGCAAAAUCUUUUAAGUUGUCCUGAUCAGCCAAAGCUGCUAUCACCUGAAUCUUGGUUGUUUUUACUAUUAAUAAUAUAGAAAUAUUUUGCCAAGAAAAUCUUUUGUCUUUUUGUGGGACAGGUUUCAGAAAUGGUCCACAGUCUCUGUAGAUACCUCUAGUAAUUGGUCUCAGAACUCAUUGCCUUUAAUCAGCCCUGGGGAUCAGUGGGUGACAGAUCAGUGCCUUUAUGAAAUGGAGUUACUAGGAAUGGUGUGUCAUUGCCUGACGUGCCUCCUUAUCUGCCAUAAUGGAGUUCCUUAUAUAUUUCCUGCUUGUCUUGUAUGCCUUUGGAUCUAGUAAGGAAAUAAGGAGAGGUUGAGAAAAUACAGAGUAAAGCUUUAGCAGGUAUCUUCCCGUUAAGUGACAGGCAGUGAUUUGUGCUUCUUUGGUUUUUAUCAUCGGUCUAAUGUGAGUCAUUCUUGUGCGUCAGGGUUGGAUCUUUUUGCCUUUCCUUUCUCUUCUCCUGUUGACUUGACCUGGUUUCUUUAGUCUGAGAAAUUGGACGUAUUUUUCUUUCUUUGAGGAAAGGGCUAGUGGAUAAAGCCCUCCCAUAGAGAGUGUAACGUGGGUAAUAUUUGGGUGCCCUUUCAGGGUUAGGUCCCACUUUGUUCAAGGAAUGCUGUAUGCAUGGGUAGAUUAUUAAUAAGAUGGUGGCCCCAGUAAAUGUUGGUGUAUGUGUGAGACUUGGUGGGAAGAGCUGCUUGCUGUAAAUAGUGGCUCCUCUGCUCAGCAGUUUUGUGAAGUCAGUUGACUUAUUCUUUAAUUUCAUCCCACCACCCAACAUAAAUUUUUUGGUUCAUUAAAAAAAAAAAACUUUCUGGAUGCUUUAUGUUUGUAUUAUUUUUUAACCAAAUUGGGUUCAUACCAGAUUAAAUUUCAAGUUAAAGAUAAUUUAUUAUGGCAGUUUAAAAAAACACAGAAUGUAAAGUGAAUAGUAGAAUGAACUCCAUAUCCGUAUCUCCCAGCAUUAACAAUCAACUUUCUGGAUUCUUGUUCUCUCUCUCCCUUUCCCCUACUUAGUUCUGGGGAAAGAGGGGCAGUAUUUUAAGACAAAUCCCAGACAUCAUACCAUUUCACUCCCAUACUUUGUUGUCAUGUUCGUUUUUCAAUUAUUUACCUUUUGUCUGUUGACUUUUCUUUCUCUUGUUUCUGAAAUAACACUUGGACUGUGCCCUGGUGAUGUUAUGAAGGUACACUUUCUGGUAGUGUUGUCCUUUGCAUGGCGCUUGCUGGGCUGGUCUUCAUGGAUCCUGAGGAAGACAGCUCUGCUGGUAUGCAGUUCACGUCUCAGUAGAACCUAGUCACCAGUAGAACCCAGAGGUAUCACUGCUACCUCGCGACCUUGUACAGUUAGGUGAAAGACUGUGCACUUGUAUACUAUGUUUAGAAGAAAUGGACUCAAAUCUAAGUCAUGAUGAUGUUUAUUAUUUUUUAAACCCAUAAAGAAACCAUGGCUUUGAUUAAGACUCUCUAAAUGGAUAUAGCUAGAUUCUAUUUUGUUUUUCUAAUUACAUAGACAGAAAACUUUUGACAUUACAAAUUAAUCAUUUAUAAGUUUGCCAUCUUUUGAGUACAGUAAUAAUUUAUUUGUGCAACAUUUCAGUUUUUUUUUUUUUAACUUUUACUUUAGGUUCAGAGUACAUGUGCAGGUUUGUUAUAUAGGUAAAUUGCGUGUCAUGGGGAUUUGGCGUACAGACCAUUUCAUCAACCAGGUAAUAAGUAUAGUACUCGACAGGUAGUUUUUCAAGCCUGACCUUCCUCCCACCCUCCACCCUCAAGUAGGCCCUGGUGUCUGUUGUUCCCUUCUUUCUGUCCGUGUGUACUCAGUGUUUAGCUUCCACUUAUAAGUGAGAGCAUGCACUAUUUGGUUUUCUGCUCCUGCAUUACUUCACUUACGAUAAUGACCUCCAGCUCCAUCCAUGUUGCUGCAAAGGACAUGAUCUCAUUCUUUUUUUUUUUUUUUUUUAAUGAUUGCAUAAUGUUCCAUGGCAUAUAUAUACACCACAUUUUCCUUAUCCCGUCUAUCAUUGAUGGACAUUUAGGUUGGUUCCACAUCUUUGCCAUUGUGAAUAGUGCUAUGAUGAACAUACAUGUGCACAUUCUUUAUGAUAGAACAAUUUAUAUUCCUUUGGGUAAAUACCCAAUAAUGGGAUUACUAGGUCUAAUGGUAAUUCUGUUUUACGUUCUUCGAGAAAUCACCAAACUGCUUUCCACAAUAGUUGAACUAAUUUACAUUCCCACCAGCGGUGUGUAAGUGUUCCCUUUUCUCCACAAUCUUGCCAGUAUCUGUUACUUUUGGCUUUUUAAUAAUAGCCAUUCUGACUAGUGUGAGAUGGUAUUAUUGUGGCUUUGAUUUGCAUUUCUCUAAUGAUUGGCAAUGCUGAGCAUUUUUCCAUAUGCUUAUUGGCUGCAUGUGUGUCUUCUUUUAAAAAAAAUUCAGCUUUUAAAAGUUUCCAUGUAAGUUAUCAUGUUCAAGUCCCACAACAGCACUGCAAGUAAGGAAAAGUAUUAAAUUCCUCCCAGUUAAGUCAGAGAAAAGUGGAAGAUGAGAGGGGAUUAGUUAAUGACUUGAUUUUAGGUCUGUGGUCUCCUAGACUAGAAGUCCUUUCUCUUUUAAAUGUGUUUUGAGUUGCUUUGGAAUGGUUUUGAAAUGGAAAUGUGCCUUGUUCUUUAUAUUUGUUUCUUCAAAGUUUUGUCUUUUGUUUGGAAAAUUCUCAAUACCUCUGACCAGGUCUUGGAGAUGCUCGGGCAAACUACACGCUUCUUGGCAUCCUAUUCCAGGACAAGGCCAGGGCAGAGUGCAUAGCCCCUCUUGGAGCCGUUUUAUUCCUGACAUUACCCUCUCUCCGCUAUGACUUUGGUUUCUACCUCUCCACUGCUACCCCAGACCCAGGCUGUGACCAUUACCAGGGAUUUUUAUUUGGGUAUGCUGGUGACUUUUGUGACAGAGUGGAAUUUAUUUGAGCCUAAAGUGUCUGGAAUUUUUCCUGGAGACUCAAGAUACUUGAUACAGUAAAGAAAUUGUUCUCAGAUUCCUCUAUCCUUGUAGACAUUUUGGUUCAAGCACUUAAUUGCCCAAUUUCUUUCAAAGGGAGUAAUUCCAAAAAAGAUUUUUAAAGUAUCUAGACAUGAACAUUCUAAUUGUUAGAUAUUAAUUUUUUUUUCUUAAGAGGCAGGGUCUUGUUCCAUUACCUAGGCAGGAGUGCAGUGGCACGAUCACAGCUCACUGCAGCUUCCAACUCCUGGGUUCAAGCCAUCCUCCUGUUCCAGCCUUCCACAGAGCUAGGACUACAGACUACAGGUGUGUGCUACCACGCCCAGCUGACAUGAACAUUCUAUUGACUUAAAUUCCUCUGGGGAAUAGAGUAAUGCUUCAGGGUUUAUGCUUUAUUCAAAACCAAAGUUCUAGUUUUAACAAAUAAAACAAAGUUCAGCUUUAUUCAGUAAAGCAUAAAAGAAAAUAAAUUUCUAUACCAGCAAUCUAAACAUUUGUGUACUUUGUUUCUCCCAAAGAGAAACAUCAGUUAAAAUUGAUUUCCUGCUCAAAUGUCUUGUCUGCUGCAGGUGUAUUUCCUAAAACAUGAUUUAUGCAUUUGAUUUAGUGACGUUACAUGUAUUUGUAGUACCGAAUAGUUUGAAUAAUAAUUGAACAUAAUUUCAUUGCAGAUAUUUUAACCAUCGGUUAUUAUUCAAUGAAUUAUUUAUAUAAAAUAGGUUAAUAUAAUUUCAAAUAUGAAGUUGCUUUGGAAAAAGUAAAGGAACACCAGCUAAAAUCAGGAGUAAUGGGUAUUAUGGAAUAUUUUCAACAAUAGGCAGUGCUGUUUUCAAACACGUAAAGUAUUCAAAGUCAUUGGUUAACUAAAUGUUGUGAAACCAAAGUUCUGGUUUUAACAAAUAAAACAAAUCUUCAAUUAGUACACUAAACGUUUAUAAAUAAUACAGGCAAAAUGAUUCCUAAAUUGCUUAGGAACAGUUUAUUUAUUUAUUUAUUUUUGUACAAACAAAAAGCUUCAUAGAAAGUCUAAUGAGAUUUGGGACUUGUUGGAGAUUUUAUGUUUUGUGGGCAUAGCUAGGCUGAAUUAGCCAGUUAUGGUCAGGGGGCUACCAAAGAACCUUUUCAUAAAUGGAAAUUGGUAGAGCCUGAUGAGACAUCAGAGGCCUUUAUUUUAGUGGCUGUGUGCAUGUGGGGAUGGCCAGGAAGAGGAGAAAAUAGCAAAGUGGAAUAUUUUUAUUUCACUGGGAAGUUGCUCUCAUAGCCUAGUCUCAGCCUUGCUGGUGUGUGCCUUGUGAUCUUAAGUAAAACACUUUGAUUUGAUGGCCCCAGUCUGUGUAUAAUUUGAGGCUUUAACUAGAACCUGCGACUUUCACAUUGGGUACUUGACCUCCCCCCAGAUACAAGGUGGUAAGCCAAGAAGUAUGAGGUAACUUGCUAAAUACAGCAUAUAUUUUUUAAAGAUUUAGGCAAAGAUUGGUUUUUAUAUUAGUACAGCCAUGACUAUAUUAUUAGAGCAAAGCACAAAAUUUACAUGUAGUUUUAAGGUAAACUAUAAACAUAAAAAACUGCACCUUUUAUUAGAGCCCCUUGGGAUGAUGCACCUAGACAUUCAGGUGGCUGUUUUUGACCUCUACCCAUAGUAUUCUUGGGAGAAAAUAUUCAGGAAGACAGUUGAUAUUUUUUAAAAUAAAUUUCAUUGUAUAUAUUUAAGGUAUAUGACAUGAUGUUAUAGGCUACAUAUAGAUAGUAAAACAAUUACUAUAGUGAAACUAUCAUUUCAUAUGUUACUCAAUUUUUGUUUUUGUGGCAAAAGGAGCUAAAAAUUUACUCAUUUAGUAAGAAUCCCAUAUACAGUAUGAUUUUAUUACCUAUCAUCCUCAUAUUGUACAUCGGCGCUCUAGACUUGUUUGCCGGUUGCUAGAUGACAUCCAAAAUCUUAUUUCACUCUUAGUUUAUAUCAUUCCUAUCUAAGAACUGAUCAUGGAUGCCUUUUCAUCUUAAUAAUCAGGUGUUUUGUUUUAUUAUUGUUUUAUGUAGUAGGUUAUUUAAAACAGCAUGUGCCAUCUAAGUAGUGUAAUUCCAAUUAUGUUAAAAUAUAUAGGCCCACUUUUUCCAUUUAUUCUACAGUACAUAUCAAGCGCUCGCUAUAUGUGAGGCACUCUUUUGGACUUCUGUUUUUGUUUUUUGUUUUAUUUCUUUUUGAGACAGUCUCGCUCUGUCGCCCAGGCUGGAGUGCAGUGGUGCGAACUUAGCUCGCUGCAGCCUCUGCCUCCUGAGUAUCUAGGAUUACAGGCACCCACCAUCAUGCCUGGCAAAUUUUUUUUUUUUUUUUUUUUUUUUAGUAGAGACAGGGUUUUGCAAUAUUGACCAGGCUGCUCUUGAACUUCUGGCCUCAAGUGAUCUGUCCACUUCUUCUUCCCAAAGUGCUGGGAUUACAGGCAUGAGCCACCAUACCCAGCCUCUUUUGGGCUUUUAAGGAGUACAUUUGCUUUGUUUAAAUAUUUAAUUAAAUUGUUAACAUUUUGAGUACAUAACAAAUUCACAUGGUUCAAAAUUCAAAUGGCAUGAAAAGAUACAUAAUGUCAAGUGUACCUCCCACCCUUGCCAUCCAGGUCUACUUCCUGGAGAUAGUGGAUGUUGCUUUCAAAGCCUUCAAGUGAUAUUGUAUGUUUUUAUUACCAAAUAUGUACAUAUCUCCUUCCUUCCCUCUCUUACACAAAUGGUAGCAUAUGUUAAAUCAAGUUUAGUCUAAAGCUGCCUCCUUAAAUAUUUUAAGUUCAGUGUAAAGGUUUCUCUGUAUAUAGUGAACUGUACCUAAAUGCAGGUGUAAACAGACUGUAACCUACUCUUGUGCCAAUCACCAAUUUUUGGUCAAUCAAAGGGGGCCAAUUGUUCAAACUGUAUUCAAAUAAGGCAAACACUAAGCUGUAACCACUCCAGCUGUUUCUGUACCUCACUUCCACUUUCUGUACAUCACUUUCCUUUUUCUCUCUAUAAAUCUUCCACCAUGUGGCUGUGCUGGAGUCUCUGAGCCUACCGUGGCUUGGGAGGCUGCUUGAUUCAUGAAUCGUUCUUUGCUCAAUUAACCUCUGUUAAAUUUAAUUUAGCUAAGGAUUUUCUUUUAGCAUAUACAAUACCUAUGAAUCUGCCGCCUUGCUUUUUUCAUUUGACAAUUAGAUUUGUCCUGAAGGAUAUAUACCUGUUAGCACUGGUUAUCUCUGAAAGAUAAGAUGGAGGAGGCUUGGCUUGCGGUGUCUGUUUAUCUGUCUGUCUAUGUAUUUAACUUUCUGUAUUUCUGUAUUGCCUGAAUCUUCUUACAGGGAGAAUAUUGCCUUUUCGAUAAAGAGGGAAAGUCCUUUUUGAAAAAAGAGAUAGCGUAAGGUAAUUAAAUCCACACAAACACAUAUAAAUCGGAUCUUUGAUUUUUCUAAUAGCUCCCUCCAUGGUGGAAGUUUUGGAGGAAGUGGGUGUAUGUGUUUGUGGAAGGCUUUUUGACCUGGGAUAGGGAGUGAGCAGGGGAAGUCUCUGAAAGAACCCCCAAGGAAUGCUUUUAUAACUUUGCCUUAAUGGUUAAGGAAAGUGAAACUACAUGGAUUUCCCCCUUUAGGCAGCAUUUGUCUCCAGGUGUGGUAACUCAUUUUAAGGAACUGAAAACACAUUCCAGAAUCUUCUAUCAGCAUCAUCGAUGGUAUCCCCAGUUGGAGGUGCACUACUCAGUUGGGGAGCACACAGGCUUUGGAGCCUAUUGUUGGGACUCCUCCGCUCAACAUGUGACCCUUUGUAGGGCACUUGACCUUGAGUACCAGGUUGCUUGGUACCAUUUGACCUUGAGUACCAGGAACCUUGAGUACCUAGGUUCCUCACCUGUCAAUAGAUAUUCAUUUAUCCCUUUUUGUAGAAUUGCUUUGAAUUUAGUGAGCUUAUACUUUUAAAAAGCUCGGGUCAUAGUAGGCUUUCAGUACGUGUUAGCUAUUAUCAUCACCCUCCUUGCUAGGCAGAGCAGGACAGUGGGGAAUUGAUGUUUCCUCCCCUCCAUCUCACAGGUGGGGCAGGGGUGUGCUGAGAAGAGAACUUGGGACUCUUGGCCCCUGUUCAAUUCUCUGCUUAACCUGCUAGGCAAUUUGGGCCUCUGAAAAUUCAGUAAUCCUCAUAGCAACUUAGACGUCACCUGGGCCUGUGGUCCCCUUCCUAGCCUAGGAGCCAGAGCAUGAAGCUCCAUCUGUCACAUUGGUUUGUUCAGAGAACUACACAUGCGUUUUAUUUUAGCAGCAUACAGGUUCCCACUUAGGCAUUGAGAGGACAUAGGAAGCUGUUUAACUUCCUAGUCUUUAAGGUGUGGACGCUGAAGAGCUUAGCUAGUAAUGACAGUAUCCUGUAGAAAAAGCUAUGGCAUCACAUACUGAUUUUCUAAUUACUUCAACCCAUAAGGAUGCUAUAAUGCUUUUGUAAAUUACCGUCUAAGCUAUAUGAAGUAAUGCAUUCCAUCCUGCAGUGCAGUAAAUGUUACUAUACUCUUGUAAGUAGUGGCAUGUGUUUCCAAAGUUGAGGUUAAAUCCAGAAAGGCUGCGACACAAUAAUUAGUUUUAUAAUUCUUCAUGCAGACUGAUGGAGAAGUCUUUACAAUUUUGACUUGCCUCUUAAGACCCCUCUAGGGUUAGUUUCACAUUUAUUUUCCAGUUUCUUCAGUGUUAGAUUUCUAUUUUAAAAGGCGGGAUUAUUUCAUAACAUAACUACCAUGUGUUAGGCAUCGCAGAAUUGCCAUCUGAUAAUCUAAACUCAAGUACAACAGCAAAGACAGCUGCAGAAGAAAAAUUUUUGAUGUCCUAUGUCAUAGCCUAAAAAGCCCCACAAGAGGGUCUAGCAAGCAGAGGAUAGUAGUUUUACAGGAGAGAACAAGUGAGACAGAGCCCUUCACAGCACAUAACAGGGGUUCGGCUCUUGCAUCAUCUGGUUAAUGUGCUAGAAAUCAAGCAUGAAUGCCUUUUGUGUUCUCAAGCUCUAAUUGCAAAACUUGUUUAUCCAAGGAAAAAAUAAAAUGAAACAAGAGAGACAUGCCAUUGGCUGUCACACGGCCAAGGUUCUCCCAUGCCUUCCUAGCUCAUCUGACAUCUUCCUCUCCUACUCCCAGCAUGCCCCUAAGUCACCUUUUUUUUUGUAAUCAGAUCUCAGGUUCCUUUAUCUUAGUUCAUAGUGAUUAUUUCGCAGAACAUGACAACUCGCUUAAAAGAACAGUGAUUGAUUUCAUGGAGCACUUAUAAAACAUAGGUACUGAGUACUUUUACAUAUGUUAUUUCAUUUAACCUUUAUGGUAACUUGAUUAAAACUUUGUAACUUUUCAGGUAGCUUUGUUUUUGUGGUACACUGAAGGAAAGAGGACUAGGGAAGUUAAAAACCUUUCCCAUGAUCACAUGGCAGAAACUGGGAGAGUGAGAACUGGAAUCCAAGUCUACCUGAUUCAAAACUUGUUCUUAGUCUGAACUUUACCAUAAUAAUAGCUGCCAUUUAUUGAAGACCUACUGUUUUCUAGGACCUGUAAAAAAACAACUCUCUGAGGUUACUAACUUAAACAAUGGAUCAAAGUUAGUGUUACCAGUAAUGGGGCAGAUGGAUAGCUUCUGUUCUUUGAUAUGAUCAGAGUGGAACACAACAUUACUUCUGGGGCAUUCUUGCCAAAAAUGCAUAACCUCAAUUUAAUCAAGAGAAAACAUCAGAGAAACCCAAACUGGAGAUAUUCGGUAAAAAAAAACUAGCACCCUUCAACUGUCAGGGUCAUGAAAGGUGAAGAAAGAUUGAGGAACUGCCACGUAUUAGCAGAGACUAAGGGGACACUAAAUAAUUGUGGGAACAGAGAAAAGGCUAUUAGAGGGGAAAUUUGUGAAAUUAAAAAGAAGAUAUGUCAUUUAGUUAACAGAAUUCUAACCAUGUUAAUUCCUUGGUUUUGAUCAUUGUACUAUCCUCAUCUAAGUUGAUAAUAUAAAGGACUCUGGGUGAAGGGUAUGCCUCAGUUUUUUGUACUAUUGCAGCUUCUCUUUAAACCUAAAAUUAUUUCAAAAUAGAAAGUAGGCCGGGCACAGUGGGUCAUGACAGUAAUAACAGCACUUUGGGAGGCUGAGGCAAGAGGAUUGUUUGAGCCCAGAAGUUCGAGACCAGGCUGGGCAACAGAGUGAGAACUCUUCUCUACAAAAAUAAAAUUAAAAAUAACCUGGCAUGGUGGCACACACCUGUAGUCCCCAACACUCCAGAGGCUGAGGUGGGAGACUGCUGAGCUGUGAUUGCACCACUUGCAUUUCAGAGAAAAGAAAAGAGAAAGGAAGGCAAGCAGGGAUGGAGGGAAGGAGGGAAGGAAGGAAGGAAGGAGAGAAAGAGAGGAAAGAGGGAGGAAGAGGGAAAGGAGAAAGAAGGAAGGAAAGGAGAGAGAGAGAGAGAAAAAGAAAGAGAGAAAGAAAGUAAGUUAGAAAAAGUUUAAAAAUCUAUCUGAGGUUGAUAUUAUUUAUUUUCAUUUUAGGAUAAAGAAACAAAAGGCUCAAAUGUUAGAUAACUUACUCAAGAUCAUACAAAUGGUAAUCAUUAGUGAGUGAAGGAAGAAAAAAUCUUAAUAGUCUUGGAGAUUCCAAGGCCCAUGUGUCUUAGUUCAUUCCGUCUUCUAUAACAAAACACCAUAGACUGGGUGGCGUAUAAACAAUUGAAAUUUGUUUCUCAGAGUUCUGGAGGCUAGAAAGUCCAUGAUCCAGGUGCUAGCUGAUUCCCUCCUUCUCCUGGACAGCUGUCUUCUCACUGUACUCUCAUGUGGCAGAAGGGUUGAAGAAGUCCUCUAGGGUCUCCUUUAUAAGGGCACUGAUCCCAUUCAUGAUGGCUCUGCUAUCAUGAUCUAAUUAUCCCCAAAAGGUCUAUAUUCAGUGUAUAGCACCACAUUAACUGCUAUGCUUUAUAGCUACCUCGUUUUAAAUAUUACUAAACAUAGCCCUAGCCCUGAGCCAAAGCCCCUUUCUAUUACAUAGUCUUUAUUUUAUACUGAAAAAAUGGCAUCUUUGUGCCUAUUGAAGAAAAGCAAUGGAUAUAUCUUAAUAAUAUAGGAUAUAUAGAUUAUAUGUGUGUGUGUAAAUAGAGCAAUAUUUAUAGAGAAUUAAGGCAAUUUAAAACAACACAUGAGAAAGUAUACAAAUCAAAGUUUUUUGUUUAACCAAGGAAAAUGAAACUAGUCAUUAUUAAGUGUUGUAAUUAAAAAAAAAUUUCUACAUCCUGGGUCUCCAGAUUAUAAAGGUCAUGUUUAUCUCUUUUUCUGCUGCCCACCUUUUCCAAACUUUCCUGUACAAGCGAUGCUUAUACUGUUUAAUUCAAAAGAUAAGAAAGCCAUCUUUUUGUUUUAUAUUAUUAAAAGAUUGAUAGUUUGAAAAGAUAUGUAGAUUGUUUUCAGACUUUAAACCCAAAAGAAGAAUACACGUUUAAAAGAAAAUCCUGCAGUAUUUUUAAAUACUGAUAAAAUAUAAUUACAAUGGAAAUCUUUUUAAACUUGAAGAAACGGAUCUUUCGGCUCUAUUCAUCUGUAAACAAUUUAAUGAUAAAUUCUGCAUAAUUCUUCUAUGUGAUAUCAUUAGAAAUGUAGUACAAAGAUCUAAUUUAAAAUCACUUACUUUCUGAGCCUCCAUGUCUUCAUCUGUAAAAUAGGUACAAUACACUAACCCAAAAUUUUUGCCGAGAUAAUUUGAUAAUCUUAUAAAGUCUUUUCAAUUAAAAGACUUCAGUAUACGUUUCUUCCUUUAAAAAAACUUUUUUACUUCUUCUUAAGACUCUAUUGUAGAGUUUAUGACUCCUGAAGUUAAUAACUUCCUUCUAAAGACUUUACAAACUUUGACCUUUGUUAUUUUGAUUUACAUGUGUGAGGCAUUUCAUGAAAAUGCAGAAAACAAGUUGCUGUUUGCCAAGACAUUGGAUCAGCUAGCAUAGUGUGGUGCUAUUUUUAAUAAUACGUAAUUCCUGUGGCCAUUUGAUAAAACUAGAAGCUCAUUAAAUGAAGCCCAGAGUGACAGUCGUAUGAAAUUCAAUUUCAUAAGACCAGGACUAUUUCAGGGAUGGUUUUUGAGAGGAGCUGUAACUUAGAUCUGUCGGCUAAAUUUAGUCUGUCAGCUCGCUGGGUCCCUCCUCUCCAUUGCUGUUUAUAAUAGAGGAUGAAUGUUUGUGUGUGUGUGUUUUUUUUUUGGUCAGAAUGGAGUGGGGAAGUUGUGUGUGUGUGUGUGUGUGUGUGUAUGUGUGUGUUUGUGUGUGUGUUUUCUUGAAGGGUCUCCACCUUUGAAAAGUCUUUAUAGCUUUUUAUUGAUUAUAAAAAUAGUAGCUAUUCAUUAUAAGAAAUAUUUGCCUGUGAGAAAAUAUGCAGAAUUGUUAAGUCACCAGGGGUAACUUGUAUCAGUUUUGUAUGUAGACCUAAAUUCUUAUUUUCUAUGAAUAUAUAUCUGUGAUAUAGAUGUCACAAAAUCAUGAUCAUGCAUUUUCUAUAUCCUUGAACAUUUUCCAAGAAGAUACUUUACAAUUGUAUGGGAUUGCUUCUAAGGGCACUGAUUUGUUUAAUUUCCUAUUGUAUAUGGGAGUUCUUCUUUUCCCCCUUAGAUUAGCUGAUACCAACUGAAACUCACAGGUCAGCUGUCAAUUAAAUGUAAUCCCAAUUCUUAAUUUCUAAGGUUACUACCAUGUAAAACUUGCCUAAUAUAAAAGAGAUAUAUGUGUAUAUCAAGAUAUACUCUAACCAUCUAGUUUUAUCUAAUAGUUUCAACCUCAAUAGUCUCAGAAAAAUGUAUUGAAAGGAAAGGAAAAGACAACUCACCUUCCACCCUGCAUUUUACAGCUAGAAAGAGACCCAGAGUGCCACUUUCUCCUUUUUCAAACUUGGCAGCAAAAAGAUACUGACGUUUAGCCAGCCAGCUGGUUAUGAUUUCAUUCUUUCUUGGACCGCCCUAUUUUUCCUUCCACACCACAGUUAAACCCCCUGAGUGGUAACAGAUAGAGAAGGUCAAGGGAUAAAGGCUGACCUGCUACAUAGGCUGUGCCAGGCCACCCUUCGAGCCUGCCCAAGCCCACUGUGGGCAACUUCUCUAGAUUCUCCUUAGCUCAUUUGCUGAGUGUGGUUGGCUUUUAUUAAUGUUAAUUUUUAAAAUCUGGCAAAAUACACAAAAACUUACCAUUUUAAUCAUUUUUCAUAUUGUUGUAGAAUCAUCAUUUUCAUCAUCUCAAACUGAAGUUGUCUGUUAAAUACUUGGACUCAGAACAAAAAGACAUCCCUAAGGCCAAAAGCAAUUGGAUCUAAAGAAAACUGAAUAAUAGUGAUAGAGAAAAUUCACGAAAGGAUUUUUUUUUCUCAUCUCCUUUCUCCAUUUAUUUACUCCAACUGCUUUUUUAGCUAAAGACAAAAGAUGCUGUAGUCAUGGGUGGCAGAACCAUGCUUUUGUGUAGGCAGUGCUCCCAAAGUUUGUUUACAGUGCUUUUGCUUGCACCUCAGAUCAUUUUUCCAGAAUGUUACGGAUUUUUUUUUUCUUCUUCUUCUUUUUUUUUUUCUUUUAGAACACUGUUCACGAUCACUUUUUCAUAUACCAUGGGACUCAGGCAAACCCUUUUUAAAUUCCUGGUUAUAUAUUUGUUUUAAUGUUCAUUAGUAUUUGUUUGUUUGUUUGUUUGUUUUCUUUAACAGCCAUCAAGGCUAGGCAUGGUGGCUCACACUUGUAAUCUCAGCAAUUUGGGAGGCUGAGACAGGAGGAUCACUUGAGUGCAGGAGUUCAAGAGUAGCCUGGGUAACAGUGAGAUCCCAUCUCUGGGAAAAAAAAAAAAAAAAGCCAGGUGUGGUGGCACAUGCUUGUGGUCCCAGCUACUCAGGAGGCUGAGAUGGGAGGAUCAUUUGGGCCCCAAGAGGUCACUGCUACAGUGAGCUGUGAUUGCACCACUGCACCGCAGCCUGGUCAACAUAGUAAGAUUCUGUCUCAAAAAGAAAAAUGCCAUCAAAUACCUGUUUUCACAGAUAUUGUUCCUUAGAACAAGACUUAGUUAAAAAAAGAGAGUGUGAGCUAGUUUAAAGAACAGUAUUAAGUAAAUAAUAUUAUAGGUGGUAUGAAGAGGUAGCAAAUUGGUGUACAAGUAAUAUUUGGGGAACAGGUUCUGAAUGGUCUUUCAGUAGCCCACACCUCAUUCCAUAGCUUUGGCACUCCGCUGGCAGCAGGACGAAGCCAGGUAGGCAGUGGCAUGGACGUUUCUGUACUGAUUCUGCUAAUGGGCUGAGGAGGAACUUGAGGACCUGGGGGAACUGAGAAAGCCCACGUCUCUUUCUAAUCUGGGUUUCUAGGAACAUACUCCAGACCUGGGUAGCGCCAUCCCUAUGAUUGUAUUCUUCUGCUGGUGUUAUUUUUACAGCUUGCAACAUUAGAAAGGAGAGAGGAAUUUUUUUUUUUUUUUUUGAUACAGAGUCUUACUGUGUUGCCCAGGCUGGAGUGCAGUGGCACUCUCAGUUCACUGUAACCUCUGCCUCCUGGGCUCAAGCGAUUCUCCUGCCUCAGCCUCCCAGGUAGCUGGGGCUACAGGCACAUACCACCAUGUCUGGCUAAUUUUUGUAUUUCUAUUAGAGACAGGGUUUUACUGUGUUGGCCAGGCUGGUCUCAAACAUCUGACCUCAGGUGAUCCGCCCACCUCAGCCUCCCAGAGUGCUGGGAUUACAGAUAUGAGCCACUGUGCCCAGCCAAGGGAGGAUUUUUAAAAGUCUAUAUUUCAGCCUGUCCCAUUUUUUGAUUCAGAUCUUAGAUAGAAAAAGGAAGUUUUAUUUUGGUGACCGAGAUAUAGGUCCUGGUUGGGUGAGUCUUUCUGAAUAAUGCUCAGUCUGCUGGUAAUUUUGUCACUUACUCAAGCUUCAGGCCUUGAGAUGGGCAAAAGAGCUCUGUUCUCUUCUGUUUUUCUUUCCUGUUGCUCUUGCCAGAACUGCCGUUGCCAGGAAGUUUGGGGCAGGUCCCAAGCAACAUGGGUUCCCAAAGAGGGGUGGGAGUAGAAAUCUCUAGAAAAUAUGACUGCAAGAGAAGGUGAAUUCCAUGACUGCCUGGCCUUGGUGGCUGUGUCACAAUUGCUGCAUAUAUUUUAAAAUGUAUAUGUAAGUCCUGGACUUGAGAAUUCUUAGGAAACCCUUCUUCUUUUCUCUCUUUUUGGUCUUUCCUCCUACUCUCUCUGUAAUCUUUAGUUUUUUGAAAGCAUAGAAUGAUAUGUAAUUAUUAUUUAUAAAUCAUGUAUAAACAAUUGAAAUUCCCUGACCCUCUCCAAUUCUCUAUCCCUGUCCCUCCGUAGCCUCUGUAUGUAUAUGUUUCUAGAUGUUUUAUGCUUACAUACACGUGCACAUAUAUAUAUAUAUAUAUAAAUGUAUAUGCCCACAUAUAUGUGAAUGAUAAAUACAUUUUUCAAUUAAUAUGUAUUUCUACGUCACAGAUAUGUUGGUAUGUACAGAUAUACCACAUUCUUUGAAAUGACCACAUGGUAUUCUGUUGUGAGGAGGCAUCAAAUUUAUUUAUCCAAACCACAGUGAAGGAUAUUUAGGUGCUUUUGGAAAUUGUGUUACAUAAAUAGGGCUGCACUUUUGAACACACAUCUUGACUCAUUUUUAAUAUAUCUGUAAGUAAGAGAUGGAAUUCCUGGGGCUUAAAGUAUAUUAUACAUUUUGGUAAAUAAUGUCACAUUGCCCUAUGACUGUCAUAAAGGUUAUGACAGUCUUAACUAAUUUUUGCUCUUAUUUAAUCUGAGCAUAUGUUAUUUGUACUUGUCUACUAUUUCAUACUUUUGGCAUAUUUUAUUCCAUAUAUUCUGCCUUAGCCUGUGCUCCUUUUUCCCCUACACUAUCAGGAAUACAUAGUGCUUUAAUAGUAGAUGUUCAAUACGAUAUGGGUUUUAGGAAGAAAAAACCUCCCUACUCAUUUGAGAAUAAUGUAGUAACCCCAAGCUCAGUGCAUUGUCCUGUCAUUUUUGUGGACACUGUUUUGAUAUUCCUUAAAAAUGGAUAGUAAACAUCAGGUAGGUACUAAGAUAUCAAUUAAGAGAAAGUACUCCUAUUCACUAGACACUAGUAGUGAUUAAUCCCACUUAAAAAAUCCACUUAUUCAUUCAGCAAAUAUUUUUUCAAAGCCUAUUCUGUGCUAAGUGCUAUACUAAUCCACCGAAGGUUUUAUAUCUUACUAUAUAUAUAUGAGUUUGGGGUACUUGAAUAGAAGUUACAAAUUAGUGUAUGAAUAAUGCCUUUGAGUGGUUCUGAAAACAUUUUAAAUUUUACUGCUGUAGUUGGCUGUGAAUGAAGAAACUUUGCCUAGGACAGACUUUAGGACUCAUUUGUCUCAGUCUCUGUUUAUGAUCUGCUGAAGAAUCUACAUUUUUCAGGUUAGAUGCUUUAUAGAAUGCAAUCAAAGUUAAAAUUUUUAGCCAUAGGUUCUAAAACUUAAACAAAACAUGAGUGAAUUGUAGUCUGUUUCUUUCUGUCUUCCCAUCUCUCUCUGGUAUGCCCUUAGUUUAAAAAGAGUUGUUUUGUUUGGGUUGCUCUGCCGUAAAGAAGGAAUUUGAAGAGGAAUCAGUAAAAAGAAGGAGAUGGCUCCAUUAAUCAAGUGUGAAAGACUUUUCCAGGAAACAGGCUAGUGUAAAAGCUGCAAGUGAAAUGUAUAAAUACAGAUCUAAGGUUUUAAAAGAAGAUACACUGCUCUUGAAUUAUGGCUCCUAAAAAAUCCAAGGUAGAAGCAAAAUCACUGAAAAUAUUUCAAGAGCUGGCAUUUGGAUAUCUUGGUUAUUAGGAGUAAACAUUUUGAAGCAAAACAUGUGAUUAAGGCUCUUGAGAAGAGGAGCUUAUCCUGCAUUAUCCAGAAGGAAGAAUCCUGCUCAAAAAUGAGGUGAAUUAAUACUUGGGCGCUCAGGAACCCUGGACAGCUACAUGAGGUGUUUAAAAACUGCCCUGACCAUCUUGCCAAACAAGUCUCUGCUCAUGAGGCCCCACAGGAUGAACGAGCCGAGGCAGGACAGUGUCCUGCCCUGUCGGAACAGUGACUGCUGACCUGCCAAGAGAGAGCUGGGGACUGCCUGCUGUCUGCCAGUACAAUGAAGGAAGUGGUUUAUUGGUCACCCAAGAAGGUGGCAGACUGGCUGCUGGAGAAUGCUAUGCCAGAAUACUGUGAGCCUCUGGAGCAUUUCACAGGCCAGGACUUGAUCAACCUAACCCAAGAGGAUUUCAAAAAACCCCCCUUGUGCCGAGUCUCCUCUGACAAUGGGCAGCGGCUCCUGGACAUGAUAGAAACCCUGAAAAUGGAGCACCAUUUGGAAGCACACAAGAACGGCCAUGCCAAUGGGCACCUCAACAUUGGCGUAGACAUCCCCACCCCCGACGGCAGCUUCAGCAUCAAGAUUAAACCCAACGGGAUGCCAAAUGGGUAUAGGAAAGAGAUGAUAAAGAUCCCCAUGCCAGAACUGGAGCGCUCUCAGUACCCCAUGGAGUGGGGCAAGACUUUUCUGGCCUUUCUUUAUGCACUUUCCUGUUUCGUUCUCACCACAGUGAUGAUCUCGGUCGUCCACGAACGAGUACCUCCUAAGGAGGUGCAGCCUCCACUACCGGACACAUUUUUUGACCAUUUUAACCGGGUGCAGUGGGCCUUUUCUAUUUGUGAAAUUAAUGGCAUGAUCCUUGUAGGACUCUGGUUAAUUCAGUGGCUGCUCUUAAAAUACAAGUCUAUUAUUAGCAGAAGAUUUUUCUGCAUAGUUGGCACGCUGUACCUGUAUCGGUGUAUUACAAUGUAUGUAACUACACUCCCAGUACCUGGUAUGCAUUUCAACUGUUCUCCGAAGCUUUUCGGAGACUGGGAAGCCCAACUGCGAAGAAUAAUGAAGCUCAUUGCUGGAGGUGGCUUGUCUAUCACUGGCUCUCACAACAUGUGUGGGGACUAUCUGUACAGCGGCCACACGGUCAUGCUAACACUUACCUACUUAUUUAUCAAAGAGUAUUCCCCUCGGCGACUCUGGUGGUAUCACUGGAUUUGCUGGCUUCUCAGCGUAGUUGGAAUCUUCUGUAUUCUCUUAGCGCAUGACCACUACACUGUGGACGUGGUGGUGGCAUAUUACAUCACCACGAGACUCUUCUGGUGGUAUCACACUAUGGCCAAUCAGCAAGUGCUAAAGGAAGCUUCCCAGAUGAACCUCCUGGCCAGGGUGUGGUGGUACAGGCCAUUUCAGUACUUUGAAAAGAAUGUCCAAGGAAUUGUACCUCGAUCUUACCAUUGGCCUUUCCCCUGGCCAGUAGUCCACCUCAGUAGGCAAGUUAAAUACAGCCGGCUGGUGAAUGACACAUAACAGCUGUACAAAGUGGGGAAAAGACAAAUUGUCCGAAGUGCUAAGAACUCCAUGAGAGAAGAUGCCAUAAAAUAAACACCUCCCUAAUCCUAUUAUCUUUCAAUGGUUACCUUGACUUAACCUAUUGAGUUACCUGGUCAGCACUGUGAUCUUUUUUUCUCUCCAAAGGACCUGCGUUGGACAACAAUAAAGAAAAAUUUAACCUAUCAUGCACUGUACACAUUUCCUGUUCAUAAGUUUGGGAUUUACAUAACCCGCAACCACCAUGUUCCUUUGUAUAUGAUGCAGCAGCAUAAAUGUAAGCUUUUAUAUCAUAAGUUCUGGUCUUUCCAGUCACAUCUGGAAAUAAAGCGUAUUAUUUUCUUGGGAAAACAUACUUUUCAUAUCUCUUGCCCCAAAGAUUGGGCUGUAAGCCAUUUUCUAGCAAAUGUCUCUAUGAAGGUUUCUAAGUACCUGAAUGGGGUUUGAUUCUGAAAUCUUUCUACCUGUUGCACCGAUAUUCAAAUAAAAAUGAUAGACACAGAAAGGUUUGGUAACUUUGGGUUUUGUAAAAUCAGCAAAGGCAGUGUUUCAAAAAGUGCAAAAAAAAAGAUUCUGUUAUAAAGUGAUUUUCUAAGUAUUUCCUAACUUUAUUUUUCAAAAUGAUGUUAUGAACACCAAAUUUAAAGAUUUUUAACAUGUCAGAGAGAAGAGAGUUAAAAUUUAAAAAUGCAUCUUGGGAGAGAAAUUUGUCUAUGUUUCUAGUGCCUUUCUUGUCUUGAUUGUAUGGUCAGUAGGCAAUCUUAAAUGUUUUUAUUUAAAAUAAAGUAUUCCUUGAAAAUAUAAAUAUAUGUAUACACUACUAAAUUUUGCAUUUAUAGCUAAAUUGAAUCAGAAGACUGCUUAUGGUUUUAAAAUUGCAAUGACUUAAAUAAUGAGGUUGUUAAUUAGAGUCAGAGCCUGUUCACAUAUUGUGAUCAGGUAGCAAUGACAUGUACCACUUAAAUUAUUUUAUCGUCGAUUUGGUAGUUCAAUUUUAACUACUCAAUGAAAACAGCCAUGAAUAUCUUUUCUUAAAGAGAGUUUUGAAAAUGAUCACUUACCUAAAACUUGAAAGCUAUGAAUUAGUUAUCCAUACUCUCAUGACAAUUUUGUUGGUGAACAACAAAAAAGAGAUCUAUUUCUUUAAAAGAUAUUUGUGCAGAAACUGCAUGUAACUCUAAGUUUUACUCCUAACAUACAUAUGUUUGGGGAAGUAUUCUAUUCUAUACUUGCCAAUGUGGAGAACAAAAUAGUUUUUUAAGAAUGAAGAAGUAUAUAUAUCCAUUCUGUAUUUUACGUGCAGCAGAAUUAUCUUCCGUAGGAUUUUUUUGUGUAUUCACAAGGUGAUAUUUGUAUUGUAAAACAAUAAUGGUGAAGGAAAUAAAAAGGCUUUUAAAAUUUUGUUUGUUUUAAAUCUUUGUAAAGUUAUUAUUCCAGAGAGUAUACUGGUAUCUUACAGCUUACCUAGAUCAUAAAUUAAUCAAAAUGCACUUUUUAAUAAAAACUGAUACUUAAAAUAAA